CAUUCCUCCGCCGCGCGCGCCGCCGAGCAGGGCGCCGCGUCCCCCGGCCCGCGCGUGGCCGCCGGAACGACCCCGGCCCGGCGCCGGCCCCGCCCCGCCCCGCGCCCAGGGGUCCCGGGGCGGGCUCCGGGCUUCGGGCGGACGAUGCGGCGGCCCGGCCGGAGCGGCGGCGGGAAGCGGAGGCGGAGGUGACGCGCCAGGGCCGGCGGGCCGGGCCAUGCAGCGCUCCAGGGCGGGCGCGGACGAGGCGGCCCUACUCCUGGCCGGGCUGGCCCUGCGGGAGCUGGAGCCCGGGUGCGGCUCUCCCGGUCGGGGGCGGCGGGGGCCGCGGCCUGGGCCUGGAGACGAGGCGGCGCCCGCGCUGGGCCGCAGAGGGAAGGGCAGCGGCGGCCCCGAGGCCGGGGCGGACGGACUGAGCCGCGGGGAGCGGGGUCCCCGGCGCGCGGCGGUUCCGGAGCUCAGCGCGCAGCCUGCGGGCAGCCCACGGGCCAGCCUGGCGGGGUCCGACGGCGGCGGCGGUGGCGGCAGCGCCCGAUCCAGCGGCAUCAGCCUGGGCUACGACCAGCGCCACGGCAGCCCGCGCUCCGGUCGCUCGGACCCGCGUCCCGGUCCCGGGCCGCCUUCGGUGGGCAGCGCCCGCUCCAGCGUUUCCAGCCUCGGCUCCCGGGGCUCGGCCGGCGCCUACGCUGACUUCCUCCCGCCCGGCGCCUGCCCCGCGCCCGCUCGCUCCCCGGAGCCUGCGGGGCCGGCUCCCUUCCCGCUGCCUGCACUCCCGCUGCCCCCUGGCCGGGAGGGCGGCCCAAGCGCGGCCGAGCGGCGGCUGGAGGCGCUCACCCGGGAGCUGGAGCGGGCGCUCGAGGCGCGCACGGCGCGGGACUACUUCGGCAUUUGCAUCAAGUGUGGGCUUGGCAUCUACGGAGCCCAGCAGGCGUGCCAGGCAAUGGGGAGUCUUUAUCACACUGACUGCUUCACCUGCGACUCGUGUGGGAGACGACUCCGUGGGAAGGCGUUCUACAACGUGGGUGAGAAAGUGUACUGCCAGGAGGACUUCCUGUACUCCGGGUUCCAGCAGACGGCCGACAAAUGCAGCGUGUGUGGACAUCUCAUCAUGGAAAUGAUCCUGCAGGCCCUGGGCAAGUCCUACCACCCAGGCUGCUUCCGGUGCUCCGUGUGCAAUGAGUGCCUGGACGGGGUUCCCUUCACCGUGGACGUGGAGAACAACAUCUACUGCGUGCGAGACUAUCACACGGUUUUUGCACCAAAAUGCGCCUCCUGUGCCCGUCCUAUCCUCCCUGCACAGGGCUGCGAGACAACCAUCCGUGUGGUGUCCAUGGACAGAGACUACCACGUGGCAUGUUACCACUGUGAGGACUGCGGGCUGCAGCUGAGCGGGGAGGAGGGACGCCGUUGCUAUCCCCUGGCGGGCCACCUACUGUGUCGUCGUUGCCACCUGCGGCGCCUCCAACCUGGGCCUCUUCCCUCACCCACUGUGCACGUCACUGAGCUCUGAGCAGGGGAAAACCCGUCCCUGGGCCGGGGUGGGUGUGGGUGUGGAGGGAGGGCCCGCGUGGGUGGCCCUGGUCAGCGUCAGGGGAGCUCCCUCCAAUCAGUUUCCCACCGAGCUGCUGUCUGCAGGGGCCGGACCCCCGCGUGGAAGCUUCUAUUUAUUCACCGUCUGUGCCUGCUCAAGUCACUUCCCUGCGGGCCCUGCCUCCCACCCACCCCAUCACCAGCUUUCCACUUGGAGGCCCCCUGUGCCCUGCAGCCUCAGGGUAGGCCGUGGGUCACCAGGCUGGAGAGGGCCCCUGCCUUGGCCAGGGGUGCGAGGUGACCCGGCUGCAUUGCUGGGUGGGAGCUGCUGUCUGUUGUUCAGGGGCCUGGCCCCCGCCCUCCCCCCCGACCCCGACCUCGCAAAGCGCACUCCCGGGCAGGGUGUGGUCUGGAAGGCGGGGCUGGCGGGGACAUGGGUGUUCCUGCAUCUCCUAGCGCAGUUCCUGCUGGUGGGUGGAAGGGUGCCUGGUUUAGGCGGGGUCCCAGGAGGGGGUGAGGGGUGACACCCUUGGGGAGGGGGCCUGCAAAGGGCACUGCCUGUGGCCACGUGGUGUCUGUGGGAAUUGGUCCUGGGGACUUUGAUGGGUGUUUGCGGCCCCAGUUGCCGCCCUGCUCCCUCUUCCAGGGCUCCUGGCUUGGGCCCCCCGACCCCCCUGCUCAGCUCGGGAAAAUCCCCGUGCGGCUCCAGCCCCGGGUCACGCUCAGGAGCGAUGAGAGGGGCGCCCUGGCCACGCUUCAGGAAAGCCUGUGUCUGCGCGCGGGGCAAGGGGCUCCACGACAAAAGGACAAGAUUUGACUUAAAUUAAGUUUUUCCCUUGAGGAUAUUUUCAUUUUCUUUAAAAGAAUAUAAUUUUCUUCUAAGAUCUUGGACCAGCCUUGUUAUUUUUAAAGCAAAUGCCGGCAAACUCACAAGUGUCUAGUUUGUCUGUUACGGAGCUGGUUUUCAGGUGGUAAGAACCUUGUGGUUUCAGGACUUUUGUCCUGAAAUUCCUCUAAAACUUCGCCACGCGUGUCCACCUUUCAGACUUUAGGGUAGUGUGGGGUUCCGUGUGUGUCCGGGUGUUAAGGGCGGUCGCCCCAUGAAAUGCAGUGUGGAGGUCCCUCCGUGCUCCCCGGGACACACUGACGGGAAUGUGGGGUCUGGACAUGGGAGGCCCUGGUCCUGAUGCGGAAUCCCCAGGGGUUCAGGGGACAUCUGGACUGAAGUCACUCGCCCCUGGGAGAGCCUGGACCCACCUCUUGGCUGCUGCUCUCCCCUUCCUCCCCCACCGUCAGGUGUGAGUUCUGUGAAUCACUCGCGGGGCUGGGCUAGGCUCCGGGAACCAGCAGGGCUGUCCAGGCCGAGCCCAAGGGAACAAACACCAGGAGGCGCCCGCAGGGAAGUGGCGGCUUCGGAGUCCAGCAGGGCCGAGGCAUGGCGCGGGCGCCACCUGGUGGGCUGAGCCGGCAAGUACAGGGGUGGUCAGGGAGCCUUAGCCAGGGACUUACACAGCGUGGAGAGCGCUGCAUCUUAGAGUGGGGCCUUCAGCAGGACCAGGGGCCACUUCUUGGAGGAGGUGAUCCCACUGGGGCCAGAGAGUAAAGUCCAGGCGUGGAGGCUCCGGUGCUGGCUCUCUCCUGCUAGCUGAGCUGCUUUUUCUUUUCUUUUCUUUUUUUUUUUUUGAGACGGAGUGUCAUUGUGUCACCCAGGCUGGAGUGCAGUGGCACAAUCUUGGCUCACUGCAGCCUCCGCCUCCCGGGUUCAAGCAAUUCUCCUGCUUUAGUCUCCCGAGUAGCUGGGACUACAGGCGCACGCCACCACGCCCGGCUAAUUUUGUAUUUUUAGUAGAGAUGGGGUUUCACCAUGUUGGUCAGGCUGGUCUCCAACUGCUGACCUCAGGGGCGAUCCACCCACCUCAGCCUCCCAAAGUGCUGGGAUUACAGGUGUGUACCACUGUGCCCGGCUUUUUUUUUUUUUUUUUUUGAGACAGGGUCUCGUUCUGUCGCCCAGGCUGGAGUGCGUUGGCACAAUCUGGGCCUACUGCAACCUCUGCCUCCAGGGUUCAAGUAAUUCUCAUGCCUCAGCCUCCCCAGUAGCUGAGACUACAGGUGUGCCCCAUGACGCCCAGCUAUUUUUUUUUUUUUUUUUUUUAAAGACAGAGUCUAGCUCUGUCGCCCAGGCUGGAGUGCAGUGGCGUGAUCUGGGCUGACUGCAACCUCUGCCUCCCACGUUCAAGCAUUCUGCCUCAGCCUUCCAAGUGCUGGGAUUACAAGUGUGCGCCACCAGGCCUGGCUAAUUUUUGUAUUUUUAGUAGAGUCGGGGUUUCACCAUGUUGGCCAGACUGGUCUGGAACUCCUGGCCUCAAGCGAUCCAUCCGCCUUGACCUUCCAAAGUUCUGGGAUUACAGGCGUGAGCCACUGUGCCUGGCCUUACUUUUUGUAUUUUUAGUUGAGAGGGGGUUUCAGCAUGUUGGCCAGGUUGGUGUCAAACUCCUGACCUCAAGCGAGCCCACCUUGGCCUCCCAGAGUGUUGGGAUUACAGGCUUGAGCCACCGUGCCUGGCCUGGGCUCCUUUGCCUUCUAACUGGUCAGUUGCAAAGCUGUCCUCUGAACUGUCCUCUCUGCUUCCUCCCUCAAACCUGCUUUGAGCCGGGUUUCUCCUUGUUGCCAACCCGGUCCUUCUCCUCCCCUUCCUUUGCAUGUGCCAUGGUGGGCCCUGUGCUUAUAUCCAUGGGGUUGCUUCACUGAACCCUGCUCCAUCCCGGUCACCAUGCACGCUCCUGCCAGCUGGCCUGAGUCAUCACAGCUUGGAGUCCCCCCAACCCCACCCAAGUAACACACUUUGUCAAAGGUCGCAGUCAAGGGACUGCAUAGGCCCUUGGGGCAGUGGCCUCACCAGGCCACACUCUGCCCUUUCUUUCUGGGCCCCUGGGCCCCGCAUUGCCUUCUGUCAGGGCUGGUGGCCACUGCUCCACCUCCUCCCCCGGAGCUGUGCAUGGCAGUUCCCUCCGUGGGAGCCACUCUCCCGGGGUUUCUUCCUCUAUGAAGAAACCUUGGCCUCUAUGAAGUCAGGCCCCAGUUGUGACACCUCACUUGACACCCAGAAGUCUUGGCCUCUGCUCUCCAAGCUCAUUUGCCAACAGCAGUAUCUCCAUUUCAUGCCCAGGGGUGACACUGACCCCAUGAUUAUAGAGAUGGAGGAUGCUGUGUGAGAACUGGGCUGAGCCAUGCCAGUGGCCUGUGACCCUCCAGCCCUGGAUGCCACCCCCCACCUGCCCAAGGGGACCCCCACUGAUGUGGUCUCUGCUGACACCUGUGCCUGUGCCUGGGGUCCCUGUCAUCCUUCCCUGGUCUGAGUGGCAAGUCUCCUGCCAUCCCUGUCCCCGCUAUGCGGUGAGCUCUUCAGCUUGGGCCCGCCUGGUGGCUCACGCUACUCUCCACCGUGCCUGGAUUAGGGCGAGUGCUGAGGCUGGAGCUGACCCUGCCCUGGCCUUCAGGGUCUUGGCUUAGUUCCACCUGCACUGGUCCAAGUCCAGCCUGGUUGCCUAGUGAAGGAUCCACAGUGGGUACAUAAAGGGCCAAGCGCUGUCCACGUGGACACAUCCUAUGUGGGCGUGAGUGCUCCCUGCAAUCCCCAGACAAGCCUGCCUCUCAGCGGGGCUCAGCUCAGAGACAUAGACCCUGGAGGGCUGAGUCUGCCUGUGUGCGUGUGUGUGUGCAUGUGUGUGUGUGUGAGAGAGAGACAGGGAUGGGGGGAGAGUGUGUGUAUCAAUGAGAGAGACGGAGAAAGUCGUGUGUGAAAGGGAUUGAAUAUUUCAGAAAAUGAAUGAGAGAGAUUGGGAGAGAUGGUGGGAGGUGGAGUGGGAGAGAGACCUGUUGUUUAAGAGGGAGACUGAGUGACUCCGAGAAUGAGGGGGAAAGAUACGGAGACAGGAUAAGCUGCAGAGAGAGAGGGAGAGAGGGAUUGAACUGGAGCGAGACCAACAGAGCCCUGACGCUGGGAUUUGGGAGGAUUUGGUGGGUUCUCAGUGACCCCACUGAGGCCUGACCCACCAGUGGAAAAGGCUCACCUCCUGUAAGUGACCACACUGUGGGGUGUAAUUGUGUGUUUGUUUGUGUGUGUGUGUGUGUGUCUGUGUGUGUGUUGGCGUCGCCCUGAUGGCCUCUUGGAGGGUCCUGGGGUGGGUGGGUCUUGGGCAUGGGGUGCCCUCUGCCCUCAUUCUUUCUUCAUCCGGGCUCCCUGCCCCUGUUGGGGUGGGAAGCACAGAUGUCAGCUUGCUGAGCUGCAGGUACCAUGACAAUCCCAAGUGGAACUGCUCUUGGGGGGCUGUGUGGGGAGGGGCCACUGGGCAGGAUUUAUGAGACCUGGGCAGAGGUGUGGGGAGCAGUGUGGGCCAGAGGGUGACUGGGGGUUGGGGUGAGUUGGGUAGGGUGCAGCUGUGCUCAUCCCUCCCACCCAGCCCCACCCUGAGGCUGGUCUCUAGCUCGUGAGCAGAGGCCGAGAGAAGGCCCUUCCCCAUCACGGGGUCCUGUCUCGUCCGGUCUGGCAGCCCUCAUCUGGCCAGGAGGCCAGCAAGGACUUCCGGUGCCACACUCGGGAGGGGUGAGGGCUUUGCUGGCUGCAGGGUUAGGAGUAGGCGCAGCCUGUGGGGCCCAGGAGAACCUUGGGGUGGGGAUCAAGAACAGGUCUGGGAGAGGGGGGAGCAUCAGGGCCACCUGCAGCCUCCACCCAGCCCAGCUCUGGAGGCUUUGCCCCCACCCCGCCCCCAUGGUAGGCGUGUUCCCUAGAGGCUGGUGGGGACCUGGGAGAGGGGCAUGUGCACACAUUUCAUGGGGAUGAUGGGGGACUCUGGGAGCCAGCCUGGGUGGGGGCUCAGAGGUGGGAGGGGCCCUGAGGCCUGAGGUGGUGGAAGGAGCUCACCUAUCUCAGGCCCAGGCCCUUGCCAGGUUCCUAGUCCCUGGCCGGAUACCCCAGGGUGGCCUGGGAUCCUGGAGAGUGCUCAGGAAACUCAGGAGGAGUGUGGACGCGGCUCCUCUCCUUCCACCCACUUCCCUGGCCCUGAGGGCAUUGCUGGGCCACCAUCCCAGACCUGGGGCAUGUGUCACAGGGCUGCCAGGAGGGCAUAGGGCCCAAGGAUUCCCCAGGGAUGCCAGCCCCCCUGUGGGCCCUCAGGACUGGUAGCCCUGGGCCCCCUGGCGCUUUGUAGGGAGGUGCUCAGCAGUGAUGGUUGUGUGCCUGUCACACCCACCCACCUGUGCCUCCCCCCACCUGCCACGCCCAUUGUCCUACACCCAGCGCACACUCCUCUCCACGCUGCGCACGUGAACCCGCCCGGGUCACACACCUGCCCUGCCAUGGUGACAGGACUGUGUGGGAUCUCUGCCUCCCUGCCUGAAGUUCCUGCCAUUGGGACCUGUCACAGGCACACAGGACACAGCUGGCUCACCCUCUUCUCUGACAGCACCUGGGCCAUCCCUGAUAGUGAUCAGCCCUGCUGAGGAAGGGUUAGGGUGGGCUGCAGGCUGGAGGCCAGGGAGAGGCCCUGGACCGGGCCUGGCAUUUACUCACCCUCCUCCCAUCCCACACUGUCCCGGAGCCUCCAUCUCCACCUGAGCCAGCUGGGUUGAUGCGGAUUUCCAGGCAUCCUCAGCGGGACCCAUGGCCUGGGGUCACCACCUUCCUGAGCUGCGUGGAUCUCAGCCAGGACUUCUCGUCCCUGAGAACAGAUUGGGGCUGGGAGUCCCAGCCCGUCCCUGGACCAGCCCUGCCAUCAGCUUGCCCAGCCUAGUUCCCUUUCUCUUCUGCGCUCUGAAUGUGCACUCCGCGUGUUCAGAUGCUCAUGGUUUCUGAUGAGAAGUUGGCUGUGUCUCUCACGGAGCCUCUCUCGGAGGUGAUGAGUGACUUUUCUCUUGCUGCCGUCAAGAUUCCUGGCUGUGGAUUGGAUGGAUGGGAAGCUCUGUCCCUGAACAGCCCUUGUGACUAUGGGGCUGUCCUUCCACAGUGUGCACUGAGGGUGCAGGCCAAACCUUUUAAAGAAUAAACAGAAAGAAAUCGGCUCUUUCACUUCUUGCAAGUUGGUGAAAACAGACUCUUCCAGGGAAUUUUAACUUUUUAUCAUCCUAUUUACUCUGGAAAGCCUUGUCUCGUGUUUUAGAGCUUGUAGGGUUUAAUAAAACUAGUUAACAGCCAGGCACGGUGGUUCACGCCUGUAAUCCCAGCACUUUGGGAGGCCGUGGCGGAUAGGUCACUUGAGGUCAGGAGUUCGAGACAAUCCUGGCCAACAUGGCGAAACCCCGUCUCUACUAAAAUUACAAAAACUAGCCAGGUGUGGUGGUGGGCACCUGUAGUCCCAGCUACUGGGGAGGAGGCUGAGGCACGAGAAUCGCUUGAACUGGGGAGACUGAGGUUGCAGUGAGCCGAGUUCACACCACUGCACUCCAGCCUGGGUGACAGAGCUAGACGCUAUCUCAAAAAUAAAUAAAUAAAUAAAUAAAUAAAUAAAUAAAUGAAUAUAAAUAAAACUGGUUAAAAAUUGAGUCUCCCUGAAGUAGGUGCUCUUUCCCGUGAAAACUACUUUUUUGGUUUGGUUUGAAGGUAAGAAAGAGCGGGAGAAACUUUGCUCUUUUCAUUUAAUAAUUGUGUUCAGCCUGGCCGGGCGCGGUGGCUCACGCCUGUAAUCCCAGCACUUUGGGAGGCCGAGGUGGGCGGAUCACCUGAGGUCGGGAGUUUGAGACCAACCUGACCAAUAUGGAGAAACCCUGUCUCUACUAAAAAUACAAAAUUUUUAGCCGGGCAUGGUGGCGCAUGCCUGUAAUCCCAGCUACUCGGGAGGCUGAGGCAGAAGAAGCGCUUGAACCCGGGAGGCGGAGGUUGCAGUCAGCCGAGAUCGUGCCAUUGCACUCCAGCCUGGGCAACAAGAGUGAACUCCGUCUCAAAAAAAAAAAAAAAAAAAAAAAUUGUAUUCGGCCUAUGAUGAAAUAUUUUAUUAUUAGAUAGCAGUGUCACUAAUAAGUUUUAAGUUGUCCAGAGUUAAUUGUGAAUAUCAGAACAGGAUUCUUAUAACAAAAGCAGUUGUCUUAAGAUGAAUGGCUCAUAUUUGGGUGCAGUAUUUGAUGCCCAAAAGAACAAACAUAAACCAAAAAAAAAAAAAAAAAAAUUCCAGACUGUCCCCUUUGGAUGCCAGUUGAAUCUGUGUCUUGUGCCCCCUGAGGGUCUGCCCGGUCACAUCCCCUUGUCUUCUCUAGGGUUCACGGGGAUCCUUCUCAUCCUCUUCUAGGUACCAGGUUCCAUUAGUUUUGUCUGUCAGUCUUGUCACCAGGGAGCUGGAGACCUGGAGGGGAGCCCUGAUGUCUGGGACAGUGCUUGUCAGUGGAUGGGCUUUUGCAUAGGGGGAUGGGGUAGGGAGUGAGUCAUUGCAUUAUAGACUUGGACUAGGUGGAUGCUAUUUUUCAUGGUGGUGGUGAUGGGAGAAGCUGUUGGGUUAUUUCACAGAGGAAGCCCGAGCUCCCUGCUGAAGAUGAUAAAUGAUGCACAGAUUUCAAUCCAUCCUACGGCUUCAGCCUCCAGUCCUGGUCCCACACAUCUCCUGGAGCAGAGCCUGAUUCCCAGCCUCUGUAGCUGGUUGAGGAGCAAAUAGGUUUCCCUGUCCUGACUCCACCUUGGAGCACCUUCCCUUGAGACCCACCAGGCUCUCUUUCAGUCACAGCAUCUUCCUCCUGCUCCAUGUGGUUGAAAUCUCAGGUCCUCUAAGGAUCCCUCCUCAUUCUCUGUUAGUGUGAGGUGGGACUUUUUUUUUUGUUUUGAGAUGGAGUCUUGCUCUGUCGCCCAGGCUGGAGUUCAGUGGCAGGAUUUCAGCUCAGUACAGCCUCGGCCUCCCGGGUUCAAGUGACUCUCCGGCCUCAGCCUCCCAAGUAGCUGGGAUUACAGGCACCUGCCAUCACUCCCAGCUAAUUUUUUAUAUUUUUAGUGAAUACAGGGUUUCAUCAUGUUGGCCAGGCUGGUCUCUAACUCCUGACCUUAAGUGAUCUACCCGCCUCAGCCUCCUAAAGUGCUAGGAUUAUAGGUGUGAGCCACUGCACCUGGCCUGUGAGGUGGGAAGUUUCAAUACUCCCUUAGCCUUGGUUUGGUCACCAGAAGGAGGGGACAUGAGUGAAGGUCCCAGUCCACCCUAUGCAAGCAGAAGCCUCUUUGGUUUUAGUUUUAAAGGUGCAUUGACCCAUGUACCUUUGCAUGGACAUGUUCUUAUUUGGGGUUACCUUUGUGUUGACUUUGUGUGGCCAGGACCCUGGAGAUGAGGCCAGGAUGGCCGACUCCAACCCCUUAGCUGCUUCCUUGCCCUGUAUGGAGCAGCUCAGCCUGGGAUGCAGGAGCAGCUGUGUCCCUCCGCUCCCGCCAGGCCUCUCCCCCUGCCUUCUGGGACUGGAAGUUCCUAGGAGUCCGGAAGUGCUGAGCUGCAGGAGGCUUCUCAUGGCCCCAGGACACACCCAUCACCCCAUCUAUAUUGAGAUGUUAUCUAGAGAGACGCCUGUAGUAAAAUCCGCUCUGUGACGGUGGUGUAUAAACAUUUUCUGUGCAAGGACCUUGCCCUCCUUUUCAAAAAAGUAAGUAUGACUCCCACAUGAAAAUUUUCUUCUACAACACGACAUACGUUCAUUGUGGUACAUUUAGGAAAUUUAAAUGAUUUAUUUCUUAUAAAACAUCAUCUGUUUUUCUACUGGACCUGGCUUUUAUAAAUCAUGCGGUGAUAAAUAAUAUGGCAGUUAGAGCUGGGUGCACUUGGCUCCUGCCUGUGGUCCCAGCUGGCUGGGAGGCAGAGGCAGGAGGAUUGCUUGAGGCCAGGAUUCCAGGCUGCAGGGAGCUAUGACUGCCAGUGCACUCCAGCCAGGGUAACACAGCGAGACCCUGUGUUAGCCUGUUUUCACGCUGCUGAUAAAGACAUCCCCAAGACUGGGAAGAAAAAGAGGUUUAAUUGGAUUUACAGUUCCACAUGGCUGGGGAGGCCUCAGCCUCCCACAUGGCUGGGGAGGCCUCCCACCAAAAGGCACUUUCAUGGUGGCGGCAAGAGAAAAAUGACAGAGAUGCAAAAGCAGAAACCCCCGAUAAAACCAUCAGAUCUUGUGAGACUUAUUCACUACCAUGAGAACAGUGUGGGGGAAACUGCCCCCAUGAUUCAGAUUCUCUCCCACUGGGUCCCUCCCACAAAAUGUGGGAAUUAAGGGAGUACAGUUCAAGAUGAGAUUUGGGUGGAGACACAGAGCCAAACGAUAUCAUUCUGCCCCUGGCCCCUUCAAAUCUCAUGUCCUCACAUUUCAAAACCAAUCAUGACUUCCCAACAGUCCCCCAAAUUCUUAACUCAUUUCAGCAUUAACCCAAAUCCAGAGUCCAAAGUCUAAUCUGAGACAAGGCAAGGCCCUUCCACCUAUGAGCCUGUAAAAUCAAAAGCAAGUUAGUUACUUCCUAGAUACAAUGGGGGUACAGGUAUUGGGUGAAUACGGCCAUUCCAAAUGGGAGAAAUUGGCCAAAACAAAGGGGUUACAGGACCCAUGCAAGUCCAAAAUCCAGCGGGGCAGUCAAAUUUUGAAGCUCCAAAGUGAUUUCCUUUGACUCCAUGUCUCAUAUCCAAGUCACAGUGAUGCAAGAGGUGUGUUCCCAUAGUCGUAGGCAGCUCCACCCCUGUGGCUUUGCAGGGCAUAGCUCCCCUGCUGGCUUCUUUCAUGGGCUGGCAUUGAGUGUCUGCGGCUUUUCCAGGCACCUUGUACAAGCUGUCAGUGUAUCUACCAUUCUGAUGUUUGGAGGAUGGUGGCCUUCUUCUUACAGCUCUACUAGGCAGUACCCCAGUAGGGAUACUGUGUUUGGGCUCUGACCCCACAUUUCCCUUCUGCACUGCCCUAGCAGAGGUUCUCCAAGAGGGCCCCUCCCCUGCAGCAAACUUUUGCCUGGGCAUCCAGGCAUUUUCAUACAUCUUCUGAAAUCUAGAUGGAGGUUCCCAAACCUCAAUUCUUGACUUCUGUACACCCGCAGGCUCAACACCACAUGGUAGCUGCCAAGGUUGGGGUUUGCACUCUCUGAAACCAUGGGCUGAGCUGUACCUUGGCCCCUUUUAGCAAUGGCUGGAGUGGCUGGGACACAAGGCAGCAAGUCCUAGGCUGCACACAACAUGGGGACUUUGGGUCCAGCCCACAAAACCAUUUUUUGCUCCUAGGCUUCUGGGUCUGUGAUGGGAAGACCAAUGACAUGCCCUGGAGACAUUUUCCCCAUUGUCUUGGGGUUAAACAUUCCCCUCCUUGUUACUUAUGCAAAUUUCUGCAGCCAGCUUGAAUUUCUUCUAAAAAAAUGGGUGUUUCUUUACUGCAUCGUCAGGCUGCAAAUUUUCCAAUUUUUUAUGCUCUGUUUCCCUUUUAAAAUGGAAUGUUUUUAAACCCAAGUCACCUCUUGAACGCUUUUCUGCUUAGAAAUUUCUUCUGCCAGAUACCCUAAAUUAUCUCUCUCAAGUUCAAAGUUCCACAAAUCUCUAGGGCAGGGGCAAAAUGCCGCCAAUCUCUUUGCUUAAACAUAACAAGAAUCACCUUUGCUCCAGUUCCCAACAAGUUCCUCAUCUCCAUCUGAGACCACAUCAGCCUGGACCUUAGUAUUCAUAUCACUAUCAGCAUUUUUAUCAAAUAUUAAACAAAUUUCUAGGAGGUUCCAAACUUUCCCACAUUUUCCUAUAUUCUUCUGAGCCCUCCAAACUGUUCCAACCUCUGCCUGUUACCCAGUUCCAAAGUUGCUUCCACAUUUUCGGGUAUGUUUUCAGCAACACCCCACUCCCAGUACCAAUUUACUGUAUUAGUUUGUUUUCAUGCUGCUGAUAAAGACAUACCUGUGACUGGGAAGAAAAAGAGGUUUAAUGGGACUUGUAGCUCCACAUGGCUGGGAGGCCUCAGAAUCAUGGCCUGAGGCAAAAGUUAUGUGGUAGCGGCAAGAGAAAAUGAAGGGUGCAAAAGCGGAAACCCUCGAUAAAACCAUGAGAUCUCGUGAGACAUAUUCACUACCAUGAGAACAAUAUGGGGGAAACUGCCCCCAUGAUUCAAAAUAUUUCCCAUUGGGUCCCUCCCACAACACGUGAGAAUUAUGGGAGUACAAUUCAAGAUGAGAUUUCGGUGGGGACACAGAGCCAAACCGUAUCAGACCCCGUCUCUACAAAAACAAAAACAAAAUAAAAAAAAGUAGCUACGUGUUUGGGCCUGGCUUUCAUUAUUUACCAAGGAUCAAGACCUGAACAUGAAAAUGGCAGGCCAAGGGUUCCUGCCUUUGGAUGCACAUGGCCACCUUGCCCACUAGAACAUCUGUGCCAAGCAGUGUUCCCAUCAAUCAUAGGAAAAUACCAUUUCCCGCAUCCUUACCAACCCUAGGUAUUGCCAAUAAGAAAACAAAGUCUGUAUCAAUUUGAUGAAAAUAAUUUGAAUGUGUGCAUUUGAUGAGCUGUGAGAAUGAGAAUCUUUUGCAUGCAUUGGCCAUGGGCUUCCCUUUUGUGAGUUGCCUGUGAAUGUCCUUUUCCCAGUUUACUAGUUUGGGAUUGAAUAUUCUUACACAUUUAUUUGGUGAAGAACUUUUAUUUCAAAUUAUGAAAGAAAAAAAUACUUGCUAGAAUUCUGAUUUGAAGUGCUUUCAAAUUCUGUGUUAAUUUGGAGCUGACACCCUUUAAUAUUGAGUCCUGGCUUUGAGGGUCUGGUGCGUUUCCUCCAUUCACUGAAGUUUUAUUUUACAUCUCUCAGUAAAGCUUUAUGGAUUAGGGUCUUCAGAAGCCUUACUUGUUUUUCUGGCUCUAUUUUCUUGUCCAGAAACUCCACCACUGUGCUAAAGAGACAGUGGUGGAGGUGCUGGGCGUGCUGCUUUUCUCCUGGCUCUAAUGGGAAGGCCAAGAGGCAGGUCAGGGUCAGACUCCACCUUGAGUCUGGCAUUGGCUGUUGGCAUCAUGAGGACCCCACGUAUUGUACUUUGAUAAAGUUAAUAAAUGGAAUUCUCCUUUACCUCAA